AUUCCAGCCGCAGAAGCUCAGGGCUCCCGCGUACCGGGAUUUUUUCCGAGCAGAAAAAAGCUCCAGAGCUCUCCUGACCUCCUUUCUCCUCGGCGGCGAGCGGAGCCUCUCCCUCGGCGCUGCCGGCCGCGCCAUGCCGCGCUCGCGGGGACGGGAGCUGGGGCGCUGCGGCUGCCCCGCGGGGAGGGCUCGCGGCGAAACCGGGAUUUCGGCGCUUGUGCCGGGCGCCGGGAGCCGCUGGGGCCGCCCGCCGCCGCCAACGCCGCCGCCUCUGCUGCUGUUGCUGGGCUGUGGGUUGCUCAGCGUCUCGGCCGCCGCGGGCCAGAACUGCACGUUCCAACUGCACGGUCCCAAUGGGACAGUUGAGAGCCCAGGGUUCCCAUAUGGCUACCCCAAUUACGCCAACUGCACGUGGACCAUCACCGCGGAAGAGCAGCACAGAAUCCAGCUUGUGUUCCAGUCCUUUGCCCUGGAAGAGGACUUUGAUGUCCUGUCGGUGUUUGAUGGUCCACCCCAGCCAGAGAAUCUGCGUACGAGGCUCACAGGCUUUCAGCUGCCAGCCACCAUUGUUAGUGCAGCCACCACCCUCUCUCUGCGCCUCAUCAGCGACUAUGCAGUCAGUGCCCAAGGCUUCCACGCCACCUAUGAAGUUCUCCCCAGCCACACAUGUGGGAACCCAGGGAGGCUGCCCAAUGGCAUCCAGCAGGGUUCAACCUUCAACCUCGGUGACAAGGUCCGCUACAGCUGCAACCUUGGCUUCUUCCUGGAGGGCCACGCCGUGCUCACCUGCCACGCUGGCUCUGAGAACAGCGCCACGUGGGACUUCCCCCUGCCUUCCUGCAGAGCUGAUGAUGCCUGUGGUGGGACCCUGCGGGGCCAGAGUGGCAUCAUCUCCAGCCCCCACUUCCCCUCGGAGUACCAUAACAAUGCCGACUGCACAUGGACCAUCCUGGCUGAGCUGGGGGACACCAUCGCCCUGGUGUUUAUUGACUUCCAGCUGGAGGAUGGUUACGACUUUCUGGAAGUCACUGGGACAGAAGGCUCCUCCCUCUGGUUCACCGGAGCCAGCCUCCCAGCCCCCGUUAUCAGCAGCAAGAACUGGCUGCGACUGCACUUCACAUCGGAUGGCAACCACCGGCAGCGCGGAUUCAGUGCCCAAUACCAAGUCAAGAAGCAAAUUGAGUUGAAGUCUCGAGGUGUGAAGCUGAUGCCCAGCAAAGACAACAGCCAGAAGACGUCUGUGUUAACUCAGGUUGGUGUGUCCCAAGGACAUAAUAUGUGUCCAGACCCUGGCAUACCCGAAAGGGGCAAAAGACUAGGCUCGGAUUUCAGGUUAGGAUCCAGCGUCCAGUUCACCUGCAACGAGGGCUAUGACCUGCAAGGGUCCAAGCGGAUCACCUGUAUGAAAGUGAGCGACAUGUUUGCGGCCUGGAGCGACCACAGGCCAGUCUGCCGAGCCCGCAUGUGUGAUGCCCACCUUCGAGGCCCCUCGGGCAUCAUCACCUCCCCCAAUUUCCCCAUUCAGUAUGACAACAAUGCACACUGUGUGUGGAUCAUCACAGCACUCAACCCCUCCAAGGUGAUCAAGCUCGCCUUUGAGGAGUUUGAUUUGGAGAGGGGCUAUGACACCCUGACGGUCGGUGAUGGUGGUCAGGAUGGGGACCAGAAGACAGUUCUCUACAUCCUGACAGGUACAUCGGUCCCGGAUCUCAUUGUCAGCACCAAUCAUCAAAUGUGGCUCCUCUUCCAGACUGAUGGCAGUGGCAGUUCCCUGGGAUUCAAGGCUUCUUAUGAAGAGAUCGAGCAGGGCAGUUGCGGUGACCCUGGCAUACCUGCAUAUGGCCGGAGGGAAGGCUCCCGGUUUCACCACGGUGACACACUCAAGUUUGAGUGCCAGCCCGCCUUUGAGCUGGUGGGACAGAAGGCAAUCACAUGCCAAAAGAAUAACCAAUGGUCGGCUAAGAAGCCAGGCUGCGUGUUCUCCUGCUUCUUCAACUUCACCAGCCCGUCUGGGGUUGUCCUGUCUCCCAACUACCCAGAGGACUAUGGCAACCACCUCCACUGUGUCUGGCUCAUCCUGGCCAGGCCUGAGAGCCGCAUCCACCUGGCCUUCAACGACAUUGACGUGGAGCCUCAGUUUGAUUUCCUGGUCAUCAAGGAUGGGGCCACCGCCGAGGCGCCCGUCCUGGGCACCUUCUCAGGAAACCAGCUUCCCUCCUCCAUCACAAGCAGUGGCCACGUGGCCCGUCUCGAGUUCCAGACUGACCACUCCACAGGGAAGAGGGGCUUCAACAUCACUUUUACCACCUUCCGACACAACGAGUGCCCGGAUCCUGGCGUUCCAGUAAAUGGCAAACGGUUUGGGGACAGCCUCCAGCUGGGCAGCUCCAUCUCCUUCCUCUGUGAUGAAGGCUUCCUUGGGACUCAGGGCUCAGAGACCAUCACCUGCGUCCUGAAGGAGGGCAGCGUGGUCUGGAACAGCGCUGUGCUGCGGUGUGAAGCUCCCUGUGGUGGUCACCUGACUUCGCCCAGCGGCACCAUCCUCUCUCCGGGCUGGCCUGGCUUCUACAAGGAUGCCUUGAGCUGUGCCUGGGUGAUUGAGGCCCAGCCAGGCUACCCCAUCAAAAUCACCUUCGACAGAUUCAAAACCGAGGUCAACUAUGACACCCUGGAAGUACGCGAUGGGCGGACUUACUCAGCGCCCUUGAUCGGGGUUUACCACGGGACCCAGGUUCCCCAGUUCCUCAUCAGCACCAGCAACUACCUCUACCUCCUCUUCUCUACCGACAAGAGUCACUCGGACAUCGGCUUCCAGCUCCGCUAUGAGACUAUAACACUGCAGUCAGACCACUGUCUGGAUCCAGGAAUCCCAGUAAAUGGACAGCGUCAUGGGAAUGACUUCUACGUGGGCGCGCUGGUGACCUUCAGCUGUGACUCGGGCUACACAUUAAGUGACGGGGAGCCUCUGGAGUGUGAGCCCAACUUCCAGUGGAGCCGGGCCCUGCCCAGUUGUGAAGCUCUCUGUGGUGGCUUCAUUCAAGGCUCCAGUGGGACCAUCUUGUCGCCAGGGUUCCCUGACUUCUACCCCAACAACUUGAACUGCACCUGGAUUAUCGAAACAUCUCAUGGCAAGGGUGUGUUCUUCACUUUCCACACCUUCCACCUGGAAAGUGGCCAUGACUACCUCCUCAUCACUGAGAACGGCAGCUUCACCCAGCCCCUGAGGCAGCUAACUGGAUCUCGGCUGCCAGCUCCCAUCAGCGCUGGGCUCUAUGGCAACUUCACUGCCCAGGUCCGCUUCAUCUCUGAUUUCUCCAUGUCAUAUGAAGGAUUCAACAUCACCUUCUCAGAGUACGACUUGGAGCCCUGUGAGGAGCCCGAGGUCCCAGCCUACAGCAUCCGGAAGGGCUUGCAGUUUGGCGUGGGCGACACCUUGACCUUCUCCUGCUUCCCCGGGUACCGUCUGGAGGGCACCGCCCGCAUCACGUGCCUGGGGGGCAGACGGCGCCUGUGGAGCUCGCCUCUGCCAAGGUGUGUUGCUGAGUGUGGGAAUUCAGUCACAGGCACUCAGGGUACUUUGCUGUCCCCCAACUUUCCUGUGAACUACAAUAACAAUCAUGAAUGCAUCUACUCCAUCCAGACCCAGCCAGGGAAGGGAAUUCAGCUGAAAGCCAGGGCAUUCGAACUCUCCGAAGGAGAUGUCCUCAAGGUUUAUGAUGGCAACAACAACUCCGCCCGUUUGCUGGGAGUUUUUAGCCAUUCUGAGAUGAUGGGGGUGACUUUGAACAGCACAUCCAGCAGUCUGUGGCUUGAUUUCAUCACUGAUGCUGAAAACACCAGCAAGGGCUUUGAACUGCACUUUUCCAGCUUUGAACUCAUCAAAUGUGAGGACCCAGGAACCCCCAAGUUUGGCUACAAGGUUCAUGAUGAAGGUCAUUUUGCAGGGAGCUCCGUGUCCUUCAGCUGUGACCCUGGAUACAGCCUGCGGGGUAGUGAGGAGCUGCUGUGUCUGAGUGGAGAGCGCCGGACCUGGGACCGGCCUCUGCCCACCUGUGUCGCCGAGUGUGGAGGGACAGUGAGAGGAGAGGUGUCGGGGCAGGUGCUGUCACCCGGGUAUCCAGCUCCCUAUGAACACAAUCUCAACUGCAUCUGGACCAUCGAAGCAGAGGCCGGCUGCACCAUUGGGCUACACUUCCUGGUGUUUGACACAGAGGAGGUUCACGACGUGCUGCGCAUCUGGGAUGGGCCUGUGGAGAGCGGGGUUCUGCUGAAGGAGCUGAGUGGCCCGGCCCUGCCCAAGGACCUGCAUAGCACCUUCAACUCGGUCGUCCUGCAGUUCAGCACUGACUUCUUCACCAGCAAGCAGGGCUUUGCCAUUCAAUUUUCAGUGUCCACAGCAACGUCCUGCAAUGACCCUGGGAUCCCGCAGAAUGGGAGUCGGAGUGGUGACAGUUGGGAAGCCGGCGACUCCACAGUGUUCCAGUGUGACCCUGGCUACGCGCUGCAGGGAAGUGCAGAGAUCAGCUGUGUGAAGAUCGAGAACAGGUUCUUCUGGCAGCCCAGCCCGCCAACAUGCAUCGCUCCCUGCGGGGGAGACCUGACAGGACCAUCUGGAGUCAUCCUCUCACCAAAUUACCCAGAACCCUACCCGCCAGGCAAGGAGUGUGACUGGAAAGUGACCGUCUCACCAGACUACGUCAUCGCCCUGGUAUUUAACAUCUUUAACCUGGAGCCUGGCUAUGACUUCCUCCAUAUCUACGACGGACGGGACUCUCUCAGCCCUCUCAUAGGAAGCUUCUAUGGCUCCCAGCUCCCAGGCCGCAUUGAAAGCAGCAGCAACAGCCUCUUCCUCGCCUUCCGCAGCGAUGCAUCUGUGAGCAAUGCUGGCUUCGUCAUUGACUAUACAGAAAACCCGCGGGAGUCAUGUUUUGAUCCUGGUUCCAUCAAGAACGGCACACGGGUGGGGUCCGACCUGAAGCUGGGCUCCUCCGUCACCUACUACUGCCACGGGGGCUACGAAGUUGAGGGCACCUCGACCCUGAGCUGCAUCCUGGGGCCUGAUGGGAAGCCCGUGUGGAACAAUCCCCGGCCAGUCUGCACAGCCCCCUGUGGGGGACAGUAUGUGGGUUCGGACGGAGUGGUCUUGUCCCCCAACUACCCCCAGAACUACACCAGUGGACAGAUCUGCUUGUAUUUUGUUACUGUGCCCAAGGACUAUGUGGUGUUUGGCCAGUUCGCCUUCUUUCACACGGCCCUCAACGACGUGGUGGAGGUUCACGACGGCCACAGCCAGCACUCGCGGCUCCUCAGCUCCCUCUCGGGCUCCCAUACAGGAGAAUCACUGCCCUUGGCCACCUCCAAUCAAGUUCUCAUUAAGUUCAGCGCCAAAGGCCUCGCACCAGCCAGAGGCUUCCACUUUGUCUACCAAGCGGUUCCUCGAACCAGCGCCACGCAGUGCAGCUCUGUGCCGGAACCCCGCUAUGGCAAGAGGCUGGGCAGUGACUUCUCGGUGGGGGCCAUCGUCCGCUUCGAAUGCAACUCCGGCUAUGCCCUGCAGGGGUCGCCAGAGAUCGAGUGCCUCCCUGUGCCUGGGGCCUUGGCCCAAUGGAAUGUCUCAGCGCCCACGUGUGUGGUGCCGUGUGGAGGCAACCUCACAGAGCGCAGGGGCACCAUCCUGUCCCCUGGCUUCCCAGAGCCGUACCUCAACAGCCUCAACUGUGUGUGGAAGAUCGUGGUCCCCGAAGGCGCUGGCAUCCAGAUCCAAGUUGUCAGUUUUGUGACAGAGCAGAACUGGGACUCGCUGGAAGUAUUUGAUGGUGCAGAUAACACUGUAACCAUGCUGGGGAGUUUCUCAGGAACAACCGUGCCUGCCCUUCUGAACAGCACCUCCAACCAGCUCUACCUUCAUUUCUACUCAGAUAUCAGCGUAUCUGCAGCUGGCUUCCACUUGGAGUACAAAACGGUGGGCCUGAGCAGUUGUCCGGAACCUGCUGUGCCCAGUAACGGGGUGAAGACUGGCGAGCGCUACUUGGUGAAUGAUGUGGUGUCUUUCCAGUGUGAGCCGGGAUAUGCCCUCCAGGGCCACGCCCACAUCUCCUGCAUGCCCGGAACAGUGCGGCGAUGGAACUACCCUCCUCCACUCUGUAUUGCACAGUGUGGGGGAACAGUGGAGGAGAUGGAGGGGGUGAUCCUGAGCCCCGGCUUCCCAGGCAACUACCCCAGUAACAUGGACUGCUCCUGGAAAAUAGCACUGCCCGUGGGCUUUGGAGCUCACAUCCAGUUCCUGAACUUCUCCACCGAGCCCAACCACGACUACAUAGAAAUCCGGAAUGGCCCCUAUGAGACCAGCCGCAUGAUGGGAAGAUUCAGUGGAAGCGAGCUUCCAAGCUCCCUCCUCUCCACGUCCCACGAGACCACCGUGUAUUUCCACAGCGACCACUCCCAGAAUCGGCCAGGAUUCAAGCUGGAGUAUCAGGCCUAUGAACUUCAAGAGUGCCCAGACCCAGAGCCCUUUGCCAAUGGCAUUGUGAGGGGAGCUGGCUACAACGUGGGACAAUCAGUGACCUUCGAGUGCCUCCCGGGGUAUCAAUUGACUGGCCACCCUGUCCUCACGUGUCAACAUGGCACCAACCGGAACUGGGACCACCCCCUGCCCAAGUGUGAAGUCCCUUGUGGCGGGAACAUCACUUCUUCCAACGGCACUGUGUACUCCCCGGGGUUCCCUAGCCCGUACUCCAGCUCCCAGGACUGUGUCUGGCUGAUCACCGUGCCCAUUGGCCAUGGCGUCCGCCUCAACCUCAGCCUGCUGCAGACAGAGCCCUCUGGAGAUUUCAUCACCAUCUGGGAUGGGCCACAGCAAACAGCACCACGGCUCGGCGUCUUCACCCGGAGCAUGGCCAAGAAAACAGUGCAGAGUUCAUCCAACCAGGUCCUGCUCAAGUUCCACCGUGAUGCAGCCACAGGGGGGAUCUUCGCCAUAGCUUUCUCCGCUUAUCCACUCACCAAAUGCCCUCCUCCCACCAUCCUCCCCAACGCCGAAGUCGUCACAGAGAAUGAAGAAUUCAAUAUAGGUGACAUCGUACGCUACAGAUGCCUCCCUGGCUUUACCUUAGUGGGGAAUGAAAUUCUGACCUGCAAACUUGGAACCUACCUGCAGUUUGAAGGACCACCCCCGAUAUGUGAAGUGCACUGUCCAACAAAUGAGCUUCUGACAGACUCCACAGGCGUGAUCCUGAGCCAGAGCUACCCUGGAAGCUAUCCCCAGUUCCAGACCUGCUCUUGGCUGGUGAGAGUGGAGCCCGACUAUAACAUCUCCCUCACAGUGGAGUACUUCCUCAGCGAGAAGCAAUAUGAUGAGUUUGAGAUUUUUGAUGGUCCAUCAGGACAGAGUCCUCUGCUGAAAGCCCUCAGUGGGAAUUACUCAGCUCCCCUGAUUGUCACCAGCUCAAGCAACUCUGUGUACCUGCGUUGGUCAUCUGAUCACGCCUACAAUCGGAAGGGCUUCAAGAUCCGCUAUUCAGCCCCUUACUGCAGCCUGCCCAGGGCUCCACUCCAUGGCUUCAUCCUAGGCCAGACCAGCACCCAGCCCGGGGGCUCCAUCCACUUUGGCUGCAACGCCGGCUACCGCCUGGUGGGACACAGCAUGGCCAUCUGUACCCGGCACCCCCAGGGCUACCACCUGUGGAGCGAAGCCAUCCCUCUCUGUCAAGCUCUUUCCUGUGGGCUUCCUGAGGCCCCCAAGAAUGGAAUGGUGUUUGGCAAGGAGUACACAGUGGGAACCAAGGCCAUGUACAGCUGCAGUGAAGGCUACCACCUCCAGGCAGGCGCUGAGGCCACUGCAGAGUGUCUGGACACAGGCCUAUGGAGCAACCGCAAUGUCCCACCACAGUGUGUCCCUGUGACUUGUCCUGAUGUCAGUAGCAUCAGCGUGGAGCAUGGCCGAUGGAGGCUUAUCUUUGAGACACAGUAUCAGUUCCAGGCCCAGCUGAUGCUCAUCUGUGACCCUGGCUACUACUAUACUGGCCAAAGGGUCAUCCGCUGUCAGGCCAAUGGCAAAUGGAGCCUCGGGGACUCUACGCCCACCUGCCGAAUCAUCUCCUGUGGAGAGCUCCCGAUUCCCCCCAAUGGCCACCGCAUCGGAACACUGUCUGUCUACGGGGCAACAGCCAUCUUCUCCUGCAAUUCCGGAUACACACUGGUGGGCUCCAGGGUGCGUGAGUGCAUGGCCAAUGGGCUCUGGAGUGGCUCUGAAGUCCGCUGCCUUGCUGGACACUGUGGGACUCCUGAGCCCAUUGUCAACGGACACAUCAAUGGGGAGAACUACAGCUACCGGGGCAGUGUGGUGUACCAAUGCAAUGCUGGCUUCCGCCUGAUCGGCAUGUCUGUGCGCAUCUGCCAGCAGGAUCAUCACUGGUCGGGCAAGACCCCUUUCUGUGUGCCAAUUACCUGUGGACACCCAGGCAACCCUGUCAACGGCCUCACUCAGGGUAACCAGUUUAACCUCAACGAUGUGGUCAAGUUUGUUUGCAACCCUGGGUAUAUGGCUGAGGGGGCUGCUAGGUCCCAAUGCCUGGCCAGCGGGCAAUGGAGUGACAUGCUGCCCACCUGCAGAAUCAUCAACUGUACAGAUCCUGGACACCAAGAAAAUAGUGUUCGUCAGGUCCACGCCAGCGGCCCGCACAGGUUCAGCUUCGGCACCACUGUGUCUUACCGGUGCAACCACGGCUUCUACCUCCUGGGCACCCCAGUGCUCAGCUGCCAGGGAGAUGGCACAUGGGACCGUCCCCGCCCCCAGUGUCUCUUGGUGUCCUGUGGCCAUCCGGGCUCCCCGCCUCACUCCCAGAUGUCUGGAGACAGUUAUACUGUGGGAGCAGUGGUGCGGUACAGCUGCAUCGGCAAGCGUACUCUGGUGGGAAACAGCACCCGCAUGUGUGGGCUGGAUGGACACUGGACUGGCUCCCUCCCUCACUGCUCAGGAACCAGCGUGGGAGUUUGCGGUGACCCUGGGAUCCCGGCUCAUGGCAUCCGUUUGGGGGACAGCUUUGAUCCAGGCACUGUGAUGCGCUUCAGCUGUGAAGCUGGCCACGUGCUCCGGGGAUCGUCAGAGCGCACCUGUCAAGCCAAUGGCUCGUGGAGCGGCUCGCAGCCUGAGUGUGGAGUGAUCUCUUGUGGGAACCCUGGGACUCCAAGUAAUGCCCGAGUUGUGUUCAGUGAUGGCCUGGUUUUCUCCAGCUCUAUCGUCUAUGAGUGCCGGGAAGGAUACUACGCCACAGGCCUGCUCAGCCGUCACUGCUCGGUCAAUGGUACCUGGACAGGCAGUGACCCUGAGUGCCUCGUCAUAAACUGUGGUGACCCUGGGAUUCCAGCCAAUGGCCUUCGGCUGGGCAAUGACUUCAGGUACAACAAAACUGUGACAUAUCAGUGUGUCCCUGGCUAUAUGAUGGAGUCACAUAGAGUAUCUGUGCUGAGCUGCACCAAGGACCGGACAUGGAAUGGAACCAAGCCCGUCUGCAAAGCUCUCAUGUGCAAGCCACCUCCGCUCAUCCCCAAUGGGAAGGUGGUGGGGUCUGACUUCAUGUGGGGCUCAAGUGUGACUUAUGCCUGCCUGGAGGGGUACCAGCUCUCCCUGCCCGCGGUGUUCACCUGUGAGGGAAAUGGGUCCUGGACCGGAGAGCUGCCUCAGUGUUUCCCUGUGUUCUGCGGGGAUCCUGGUGUCCCGUCCCGUGGGAGGAGAGAGGACCGAGGCUUCUCCUACAGGUCAUCUGUCUCCUUCUCCUGCCAUCCCCCUCUGGUGCUGGUGGGCUCUCCACGCAGGUUUUGCCAGUCAGAUGGGACAUGGAGUGGCACCCAGCCCAGCUGCAUAGAUCCGACCCUGACCACGUGUGCGGACCCUGGUGUGCCACAGUUUGGGAUACAGAACAAUUCUCAGGGCUACCAGGUUGGAAGCACAGUCCUCUUCCGUUGUCAAAAAGGCUACCUGCUUCAGGGCUCCACCACCAGGACCUGCCUCCCAAACCUGACCUGGAGUGGAACCCCACCUGACUGUGUCCCCCACCACUGCAGGCAGCCAGAGACGCCAACGCAUGCCAACGUCGGGGCCCUGGAUUUGCCCUCCAUGGGCUACACGCUCAUCUACUCCUGCCAGGAGGGCUUCUCCCUCAAGGGUGGCUCCGAGCACCGCACCUGCAAGGCGGAUGGCAGCUGGACAGGCAAGCCGCCCAUCUGCCUGGCAGAGGUCCGGCCCAGUGGGAGACCCAUCAACACUGCCCGGGAGCCACCGCUCACCCAAGCCUUGAUUCCUGGGGAUGUUUUUGCCAAGAAUUCCCUGUGGAAAGGGGCCUAUGAAUACCAGGGGAAGAAGCAGCCAGCCAUGCUCAGAGUGACUGGCUUCCAAGUUGCCAACAGCAAGGUCAAUGCCACCAUGAUCGACCACAGUGGCGUGGAGCUGCACUUGGCUGGAACUUACAAGAAAGAAGAUUUUCAUCUCCUACUCCAGGUGUACCAGAUUACAGGGCCUGUGGAGAUCUUUAUGAAUAAGUUCAAAGAUGAUCACUGGGCUUUAGAUGGCCAUGUCUCGUCAGAGUCCUCCGGAGCCACCUUCAUCUACCAAGGCUCUGUCAAGGGCCAAGGCUUUGGGCAGUUCGGCUUUCAAAGACUGGACCUCAGGCUGCUGGAGUCAGACCCCGAGUCCAUUGGCCGCCACUUUGCUUCCAACAGCAGCUCAGUGGCAGCCGCGAUCCUGGUGCCUUUCAUCGCCCUCAUUAUUGCGGGCUUCGUGCUCUAUCUCUACAAGCACAGGAGAAGACCCAAAGUUCCUUUCAAUGGCUAUGCUGGCCACGAGAACACCAAUGUUCGGGCCACAUUUGAGAACCCAAUGUACGACCGCAACAUCCAGCCCACAGACAUCAUGGCCAGCGAGGCGGAGUUCACAGUCAGCACAGUGUGCACAGCAGUAUAGCCACCCGGCCUGGCCGCCACCACCGCCACCGAGAGCCCCGCCUCCAGCAGCCGGUGAGCAGGGGUGUGGGAGGAAGACAGGCCAUGACAAGCACAGACAGGGACCUAUGCGUGCCAGGGGCUCCACCCAACGGAGUCGCACACACCACAUAGACACACCCAGUAAGAGGAGAGCUGUGCAUUGAGCAUCAUUGUGUAACAGGCACUGAACCAGGCCCUUUGUGGAUCUAAUAUAUUGAAUCCCUGCACGCCCUGUGAGGUAGAAGCUUGUGGGAGCCCCAUUACAGAUGAGAAAACUGAGCUGCAUAGAAACUAACUUGAGCAAGGUCACACAGCUCAGAAGGGGUGGGGUCGAAAUCCAAUCCCAGGCUGACUGGCUCCAGAAACUGCUCCUCACCCCUGGGCUUGGCAGAACAUCGGCAUGUACUAGUCUGUUUCUCUCUAGAGAAACAGAACCAACUGGAUAUAUACAUCCUCUGGGUCGAAGUCAAGCCCUGGAGAUCUGUAGAGCUAUACAGAGAUGCACAUAUAUCUGUGUAUAUAGGUAUAUUGUGUAUAUAUAUACAUUCAUACACUAUAAACGCAAUACAUAUACCCCAUAUCAAGAUAUAUCCAUACCUAUCCAUCUAUAUAUAGAUACGCAUCUCCGUAGAGCUAUAUGUAAAUGUUAUAUAGAGAUAGAAAUAUAAAUAAAUAUAUAUUUAGAGAGAGAGAUUCAUCUAAGGAAUUGGCUGGCAAGGUGGAAAUCUAAAGGGCAGGCCAGCAGGCUAGAAAUUCCAGCAGGAGUUGAUGCUGUCAUCUUGAGUCCAAAAGCAGUCAGAGACGGAAUUCCUUCCUCUUUGGAGCACCUCAGUCUUUUUCUUAAGGCCUUCAGCUGAUUGAACGAGGCCCACACACAUUAUGGAGACUCAAAGUCUACUGAUUUCAAAGUUAAUUUUAUCUAAAAAGAUACCUUCACAGCAAUAUCCAGAUUGGUGUUUGACCCAUCAACUGAGCACCAUAGCCUAGGCAGGUUUACUUACAAAAUUCCCCACAUUGAGCACAACAGAGGGGAGGAGCUCCCGGAAAUAUAGACAGGGGGCAGACACACCCACACGUGUACACGGUCAUGCACACACACACACACACAUACGCAUACAUGCACACAGGCAUGCAUCUGACAGGCCCACUGGGAAGGAACUGAUGAAUCUAAAAGGCACUGCCUCUUCCUCACUGUGUCCUCCUUCGAUGACACCCUCACCUCUGGGACCUAUGACCCUUCAGGAGUUGCCCCAACACGAUGUCCAAGCUGCACCCCUCUGAGAACUGUCUUCUCCCACACAUCCCGCUUUCUGGGGAUAGGCAGGUGCCCCCUCUCAGGUCCUGUGCUGAAGGACUCUGGGGAGAAGAGUCACAGAGCCAGCCAGGUAGGGAUUCCCAGUGAGGGCGGUGGAAAAUCCGCCAAGUGGGCCACCAGCCAAACCCAGGGCUAGUGUUGCGCUCCCUCCCCACGCUCCUGUGCAUGGCCGCUCACGUGGCAGAUUCUCCCAGCCACACACAAAUGGCAGUGCAGCGAGGAAACAGGCUUUUAUGAGGGUGCCUGCAAAGGCCACCAACAGAGAUGGUGGGGACAGUUCCUGCGGAGGGGGUUACAAGAGCAGCAAAUGUCAUUAUCACUGCCCAGCCCCUGACGUGCUUUACUCCCUUUCUGCCUCACAACUCCUGGAGGAUUUCACAGUUUCAGCCUGAGUCCCAGAUGGUGAGUGAGUCAGGGACUCAGCAGAUGCAGCUCCUGAAUACAAACAAUUUAUGGAAAGAGCUUUUCCCCAUCUUUUUACGUCUCUCCAAAACAAACAUUUAAAUAAGGGUUCCCCCUUAUUCCAGUGGGAUUGUUUUAGCAUGCCAAAAUUACUCCUCAAGUUUCAUCUGUAUGCCCAAUCUUUAUUUUUUCCUUCUCAGAACUCUUAUCAAUAGAAGGCAAAAGAGAAAAAGAAAAAUCCCCUCUGAUGAUGUAAAUCGGGGCUUGGAGAUGAUCAGUGAUGAAUCUGAUUCACUGCAUGAAUUAUUGAACAGUGUAAGAAAGAAACAAGAAUGCCGCUGACCUCCACACAGUCACUCUUGCUCCACACCUGGGUUCUGCUGGGUUCCAGGUGCUGGUGUGCGCCAUGCUGUCACCUCCGGGUCGGCUGGGGUUGGUGGCUCCACAUCUGGCCAGCCCUCAGCAUUGGCCCCUUGCCAGCAGGCUCUGAACCCACUGCCCAGCCCACAGGUCUCCAGCAGGGCCCCUCUGACCACUUCUGCCCACAGCUGGAGCAUAAAGAAAGCAAGAGCCACCCUGAACAGACACACACACAUUGCAAAUGAGUGACUAGAUGGUAAUUUUUUUUUAAAUAAUGCCAAGGAGAAAAGCUGAAAUUAAAAUAAACACCCUACUAAGGAAGCAACGAGGCCUGUGCGGUCAGUGAGUAACAGGGCGGGGGAACAGGGCUGUGUGAUGAUGUUUGCCAACCCUUCCUCCAUUAAAAAAAAGUAUCAAAAAUGAGAUUUCACAACUGUGUCACUACAAAAAUGAAUAUAAUCCAGCCUGGAUUCUUUAUUACAGAGCCAUUAUUAUCCUAGUCAUUUUUUUUUUUUCAUCUGAUUUUGAAAGAAACUAAAAUUAGAAUGUUUUCCUGGGUUCCUAAAAGUAUGGUGGCCCCCAAGCACUGGGCCUCCAGGUCUAAUGGCGAAGUUGGCCCUGCAAGGGAAAAAGACAGAAAAAUACAUGUUCUGCUGCACGUAUUCCCUACCUACCCCCAUCCCCAACCUGGGAAGAUUAAAAAUCAAAGUGAAGAUUGAGGUGACUCAUCUCUUUCCCGCUUGUGCCUUCUUUUCUUUGCCGCUUUGCUUUUCCUCCUCUGCUCCCGGCCCCUCCCCUCCCACUGCCUCUUUUUUCUUUGCAAACUCAGGUGUGAUCUGUUUGUUCCCAGUUCCCCAGGGGGCAGGAAGUAGGCUCCCCUGAGCACAGUGCCCAGUGCCCAUCUUCGUUCGUCUCCUUGCCUGUGUCUGCUACUGCUGGGACUCAGGCCCUCGCCCUGCCGCCAUCUAUGCCAGUUACCCUGGAGAGGACUCCUGCCGUGUCCUGAAAAGGCAGAAAAGGAAGAGGGGCUGCAGACAGAGGAAGAAAGUUUAUGGAUUUAAAAUAGCAAAGCAACUUGUGGAUCUGUGUGUGUGUGUGUGUGUAUGGGCCUGAUCACACACAAACACACACACCUCUCCUUCAUUCACGUCCUAUGGAAGAGACCAUAAAGGCUUCAAAACUAGAAGUGCGCAUGAAGGAUGCUUCAUGCCCUGUUCCCCACACAGAGAAGAGAUGAAGAGGGGGAGGUACGGUCAGCUUUCAAAACAAUAUGCCCCCCGCCCAUCCCAUGUGUGAGGACAUGGUGACUCGGUGACUGUAACAGUAGGACACAUCCCAUCAUGCGGUCAGAGUGCAGAAACCCGGUCAGCGUGCAGAAACCAGCUGUCUGCUGAUGAACGGCCCAUCUGCACAGCGGCAGCAAGGAUUACCCCAAGGGCAGGAAAAAAGUCUUUGGAAAUAGAUUGAAAAUCAGUUUCUUUAUUUUUUUCAAACACUGUUUUAUUGAGUUCUAAACCCAGUGGAUUAAAAAGUCAUUUGGGUCCUGGGAAGCACUGGGAAAGAAGGGAGAGCCGGGGAGGAUAGGGCAGGAGUCUGGCCAGGAGCCCAAGGUCAAGUCUGGCUGUCAACUGACAAAGAGAAGAGAAGACAAGUCUGUGGCCCAGACAGGAUGCCAAGUCUGGGGGCAGCAGCAGGGUCCUUGAGAGAACAGGGGAGCAAGCCUGCCCCAGUACCCAAAAAACAAUGGCUAUCAUGUACUGGGGUUAUUCUCUGUGCCUGACACUUUACCUGUAGUAUUUCUAGUCUGCACAAUAACACCAAAAUGUAGGAUUUGUUAUUCCCCUUUGACAGAUGAGAAAACAGAAGCCUGCAAAGGUAAAGACAGAGUUAGGAAGUGUGGAGUCAGAAUGCAAACCCAGAUCAGUCUGCCCCAAAGUCCACUACACCAGCUGCCAGAAACCCUGUUCUAGAAGGGGCAGCUAAGAAGGGAGGAGCCGAUGAAUCUCUACAGUAGCACUGUGGCCAGGUCUGGAAAGCCAGGCAAGACACCUGUGUGUCCUAUCUGGGUUCUGCUGUCUCCGCGUAGGCAGCUUCGGGGCAAGGAUUCAACUCCCCAGGCCUCCCACGGUUGGUGCUGGCUCCUUGGCUCCCAGCAGCCGCUGACCAUAGCCAGCAAAAGACCUGGCAGGUCCUGAAUCAAAACAACAGAGUGGCUGAAAGUCACACCUCUCCAGCUCCUUGCGAGUGGGUUUGAUUGAUUUUGACAGCUAUAUCAUGCUUGGGUCGUUCAUGAAUUCCAUGAGAAUUGUUGGGAAGUUCAUGAGUUUAGGAAUCAAAGUAUAGCAUUUAGGGCCACUUUCUCUGUCCUCGGGAAGGCCCCCACAAGCUUAAGCCCCUGUAUACGUGUGACAUGCUGGCCUCAGAGAUUCAUGUCACAUAUUGAAAUAGCAAAUAGAAAUGUGCAGGAGCGGAGGGACAGCGACACCUGGUUCUUAAGCAAAUUCUAGAUUGGAACAAUUAGAAGAUCUGACUGAUGUUAAGAGUGGCCAGAGGAAAGUGAGAGGCGUCCAUUUCCAGCAGACACAAUGGAGGCUGACAGAGGCAGGAGCCUACCCCUGGCCACACCACCUCUGGGACACGGCACCCCCCUGGGCCUGGAGGGAGAGGGCCAAUCCAGACACACUCACACUCUCAUCUCUUUCCUUGGCUGGAAACAAGUGCAGGAAGCUCCCCUCCCAAUUUCUUAUGCUCCCUUCCCCCUUACACUCCUCUCCUUCGACUGCUCCCUUCCCCCUUCUUAUGCCCCUCUCAGACCACCCAGCGGAUGCCUAUUCCCGCCCCCCACCCCUCCCCUGCGUCUCCUUGUAAAGUUCCAUGAGAUGCUCGAGGAGCACCUGCUGGUGGGGCACCCAGCACUCUGCUGGGCAUCACCCUCCGCACCCCUGACAUUUCUCUCCACCUCCAGAGGCUUGGAAGGGAACAGGGCAGAUGAGGCCCUUCACCCACCAUCUACGCCAUAUACCCAUCACCAUCCCAUGAGGAAAAAAAAAAAAGUAAAACAAAGACAAAAAAAAUCUUUUGUACAGAGAUAUAUUUUUAUUAUACAAAGUUUGUACAGUACCAAAAAAGAAAAAAAAAAAGGUGUAAAUUUUUUUUUCAUUAUUGUAGGUAAACGGUAGUGGAAGCCUUUUUUGUAAAUGUAAUAAAAUGUAUAAAUAUGGUUUUCAGAAAACAUCAAGUGCUGUAAAUAUGUAAUCUACACACCUUCUUGGCUUGUCUGCAGUAUAUACAUUUAAUUUAUCUGUCUCUGUAUAUGAGGCUUCCCCCUGGGGUCCUGCAUUAUGGUACUUUCCUGAAUUUGAAAGCAAUUUUAAAUUUUUUGAAUUCAAAUAAAAUAUAAAUUUUUGCAUUGGUUUUCUUACA